AUGCCUGAGCAGCACAAGGACCCCAGAGUCCAAGAAAAUCCUGAUGAUCAGAGAACGGUCCCCGAGGUCACCGGGGAUGCACGGUCUGCAUUUUGGCCCCUGCGGGACAAUGGAGGCCCCUCUCCCUUUGUGCCCAGGCCCGGGCCUCUGCAGACAGACCUCCACGCCCAGAGCUCAGAAAUCAGAUAUAACCACACAUCCCAGACAUCCUGGACGAGCUCGAGCACCAAACGAAAUGCCAUCUCCAGCUCCUACAGCUCCACGGGAGGCUUGCCGGGGCUAAAGCAGAGGAGGGGGCCAGCCUCAUCCCGCUGCCAGCUGACCCUCAGUUACUCAAAGACAGUGAGUGAGGACAGGCCUCAGGCUGUCUCUUUGGGUCACACACGGUGUGAAAAGGGGGCAGAUACAGCACCAGGGCAGACAAUCGCCCCAACGGGUGGCUCCCCCAGAUCCCAGGACUCUAGGCCCCGUAGACGCAAGAUUCCCCUGCUGCCACGCAGGCGAGGGGAGCCUUUGAUGCUGCCACCUCCCUUAGAGCUGGGGUACCGGGUCACGGCUGAAGACCUGCACCUGGAAAAAGAGACGGCAUUCCAGCGCAUCAACAGUGCACUGCACGUUGAGGACAAGGCCAUCCCGGACUGCAGACCCUCACGGCCUUCCCACACUUUGUCCUCACUUGCAACAGGGGCUUCGGGUGGGCCUCCCGUUUCUAAAGCACCCACUAUGGAUGCACAGCAGGACAGACCCAAGUCCCAAGACUGCCUGGGCCUAGUGGCCCCCCUAGCAUCUGCUGCAGAGGUCCCCGCUACAGCUCCCGUGUCUGGGAAGAAGCACAGACCACCAGGACCCCUGUUCUCCUCCUCAGAUCCCCUUCCUGCCAACUCUUCCCACUCCCGGGACUCAGCCCAGGUCACCUCGAUGAUUCCUGCCCCCUUCACAGCUGCAAGCAGGGAUGCCGGCAUGAGAAGAACAAGGUCGGCUCCUGCAGCUGCCGCAGCAGCCCCUCCCCCCUCCACAUUGAACCCCACGUCGGGGUCACUACUCAAUGCAGUGGAUGGAGGCCCCUCACAUUUCUUGGCCUCAGCCACAGCUGCAGCACGUGCCCAGAGGUCAGAAGUGAGAUAUAACCAGAGAUCCCAGACCUCCCGGACCAGAUCCUGCCUCAAACGAAAUGCCAGCUCCAGCUCCCACAGCUCUACGGAAGGCCUCCAGGAAGUAAAGCGGAGGAGGGGGCCAGCCUCAUCCCACUGCCAGCUGGCCCUCAGUUCCUCAAACACAGUGAGUGAGGACGGACCUCAGGCUGUCUCUUCGGGUCACCGCUGUGAAAACAAGGCAGGUACAGCACCAGGGCAGACACUUGCCCCCAGGGGUGGCUCCCCCAGAUCCCAGGCCUCUAGGCCCCACAUCAACACUGCACUGCACGUUGAGGACAAGGCCAUCUCGGACUGCAGACCCUCACGGCCUUCCCACACUUUGUCCUCACUUGCAACAGGGGCUUCGGGUGGGCCUCCCGUUUCUAAAGCACCCACUAUGGAUGCACAGCAGGACAGACCCAAGUCCCAAGACUCCCUGGGCCUACUGGCCCCCCUAGCAUCUGCUGCAGAGGUCCCCUCUACAGCUCCCGUGUCUGGGAAGAAGCACAGACCACCAGGACCCCUGUUCUCCUCCUCAGAUCCCCUUCCUGCCACCUCUUACCACUCCCGGGACACAGCACAGGUCACCUCGCUGAUUCCUGCCACCUUCACAGCUGCAAGCAGGGAUGCCGGCAUGAGAAGAACAAGGUCGGCUCCUGCAGCUGCCACAGCAGCCCCUCCCCCCUCCACAUUGAACAACACGUCGGGGUCACUACUCAAUGCAGUGGAUGGAGGCCCCUCACAUUUCUUGGCCUCAGCCACAGCUGCAGCACGUGCCCAGAGGUCAGAAGUGAGAUAUAACCAGAGAUCCCAGACCUCCCGGACCAGAUCCUGCCUCAAACGAAAUGCCAGCUCCAGCUCCAGCUCCCACAGCUCUACGGAAGGCCUCCAGGAACUAAAGCGGAGGAGGGGGCCAGCCUCAUCCCACUGCCAGCUGGCCCACAGUUCCUCAAACACAGUGAGUGAGGACGGACCUCAGGCUGUCUCUUCGGGUCACCGCUGUGAAAACAAGGCAGGUACAGCACCAGGGCAGACACUCGCCCCCAGGGGAGGCUCCCCCAGAUCCCAGGCCUCUAGGCCCCACAUCAACAGUGCACUGUACGUUGAGGACAAGGCCAUCUCGGACUGCAGACCCUCACGGCCUUCCCACACUUUGUCCUCACUUGCAACAGGGGCUUCGGGUGGGCCUCCCGUUUCUAAAGCACCCACUAUGGACGCACAGCAGGACAGACCCAAGUCCCAAGACUGCCUGGGCCUAGUGGCCCCCCUAGCAUCUGCUGCAGAGGUCCCCUCUACAGCUCCCGUGUCUGGGAAGAAGCACAGACCACCAGGACCCCUGUUCUCCUCCUCAGAUCCCCUUCCUGCCAACUCUUCCCACUCCCGGGACUCAGCCCAGGUCACCUCGCUGAUUCCUGCCACCUUCACAGCUGCAAGCAGGGAUGCCGGCAUGAGAAGAACAAGGCCUGGCACCUCGGCUCCUGCAGCUGCCGCAGCAGCCCUUCCCCCCUCCACAUUGAACCCCACGUCGGGGUCGCUACUCAAUGCAGUGGAUGGAGGCCCCUCACAUUUCUUGGCCUCAGCCACAGCUGCAGCACGUGCCCAGAGGUCAGAAGUGAGAUAUAACCAGAGAUCCCAGACCUCCCGGACCAGAUCCUGCCUCAAACGAAAUGCCAGCUCCAGCUCCCACAGCUCUACGGAAGGCCUCCAGGAACUAAAGCGGAGGAGGGGGCCAGCCUCAUCCCACUGCCAGCUGGCCCACAGUUCCUCAAACACAGUGAGUGAGGACGGACCUCAGGCUGUCUCUUCGGGUCACCGCUGUGAAAACAAGGCAGGUACAGCACCAGGGCAGACACUCGCCCCCAGGGGUGGCUCCCCCAGAUCCCAGGCCUCUAGGCCCCGCAUCAACAGUGCACUGCACGUUGAGGACAAGGCCAUCUCGGACUGCAGACCCUCACGGCCUUCCCACACUUUGUCCUCACUUGCAACAGGGGCUUCGGGUGGGCCUCCCGUUUCUAAAGCACCCACUAUGGAUGCACAGCAGGACAGACCCAAGUCCCAAGACUGCCUGGGCCUACUGGCCCCCCUAGCAUCUGCUGCAGAGGUCUCCUCUACAGCUCCCGUGUCUGGGAAGAAGCACAGACCACCAGGACCCCUGUUCUCCUCCUCAGAUCCCCUUCCUGCCACCUCUUCCCACUCCGGGGACUCAGCCCAGGACACCUCGCUGAUUCCUGCCCCCUUCACACCUGCAAGCAGGGAUGCCGGCAUCAGAAGAAUGUUUCGUGUUCGAAAUUGUUUGAGGGGUUUGGGUUUAUUUUUGUUGGUUUUUUCUUUUUUUUUUUUGCUUACGUGGGCAUCCUUCAGCUUUUAAUAAUCUGAAAAAUUCUAUUUACCCAUUGUCAAUGUGUAUAAAUUAAUCUCAGUCAAUUUUAUACAAUAAAAGGUGAACUUUUAUCCAUCAAACAAUAAUUUAACAAAAAAUGUACCGGAAGAAGAAUGUUCAUUACAAAUAUAGGAAACAUAAAUAUUACCAAAUAUUGGCAAGCACUAAAAUGUUCAGAAAUAUAAGUCUAUUACAGUUAUAGCUCUCUCAAGCAAAAAAACAGCAGAGAAAAACUUAGUUUUCCUGAGGGGCUAUUUAUUUACUUAGGGAUUUGUUAAAAGGUCAAAUGGGGUCACACAGAAUACUAAGAAGAGCUGUUCACCCAGGCCUCACUAAGAACUCUUCUUCAUGCAGUAGCUAUAUAGUAAUAUGACAACUGCUCCUACGACCCAAAGAGGAACUACAGCAACUACUCUUUAGCAUCUGUUGCUCCCAACUCUGCUUUGCAAUUAUAUGACUCAAGCAUUCUGGCUCCGUUAACUAUUACUGCUGUUACUCCCAAGUAAAUUCCCUCUAAAAAAUAAAAAUUUUUAAAGCUGUAA